AUUCCAGGAAGUUUGCAUAGCUCCCUGGACUUCUGCUUUGCACUGCCCUGCAGGAGUGGGUGGGGAAAGGAAGUGGCUUUGAGGCACACAGAGGGGCUUGGUGAGGCCACCGGAGGAAGCUUCUGCCACCAAUAUGGGACCUGUGCCCAGCCUACCAGAAGAGAGCAUCUGAAAACAUGUAUCGACAUGGUAACCCCUCUGCUUGAAGCCUCACAUGGCUCCCUAUUGCCUUGGUGCUGAACACCCUAUGGCUGACCGUGGCCCAGCCUCUGCAACAGCUCUGCCUCCUCUCCAGUGGUGAAGACCCAGCCUGCUGAGACUCCUCCUGCAGUUCCUCAACAUGCCUGCAUUUCUGCUGCCUCAGGGCCUUUGCGAAGGUUGUUCCUUGUAACUGGAAUGCCCUUCCAUCCCUUUUUUAUUCAAAAGGCUGCAAUUUUAAUUGAAGAAAGUUCCCUUCCAAGGUUCAUGAGUUGCCUGACUUGCCCACCGGUUUCCUGCAAGAUCCCUUGGCCUGGCACUUAGUGCUCAGGAAAUAUUUGGUGAUGGGCCAACUGAGUGAGAAGGUGGGAUCUGGUGGGAAGGAAAGCGGAAAGGUAGAAAUUCUGCUCACUUCCUCAUUCCCACCUCCCAAGGAACCCCUGGUGUCCCUGUGGAACCCGCUUUGGGAACCGGUGGUUCAGGUCAGCCUUUUCACUUUGUACUCAAAGCCACAUCGCAUUGAAGCCACAGGUGGGGCAAGGUCAUGCAUGACCUGAGUCUCCAAAUCCCUUCACCCUGUUUGGUUCUGCAACGGGGAUUAGGGGAGCCCCACGAUUUGUUUUCAAAGGAUGUCCGGGCUCCAGGACAGGAUGCCCUGGGUCACCUGAUGACAGGUGUGGUGGUUGGAAAGGGCCUGGUUUCAGCUCCGGGUACACUUCCUCCUUCCUUCUGCUGCGUGGUGUGGCCUCUUCCACGUCCUCAGAAUCCAGCUGUUACUCCGUCCGCGGCCUCUCAGCUCUAGGGCCCUCUGCACACUGGCCCCCCCAGUGGGUGUCUGUCUGUCUCUCUUGCAGAGCUCUGCGGUAGAAUCCCGUGCCCCCCGACCCCAUCAGCAGCCUACACCCCUUCAUCCUUCCUGGCCCCGGAUUUUCUCUGCCUCUGCCACUCCCGGUGGUAAAAGAGGGCUUAGAAUGCGGUUUGCUUUCUGGCUUUGUUUUUUUGCAUCCUGAUCUUUGUGGCGUGGAUCGAUCAUUUUCCAGGGAAAGUACCUUGGUGUCACGGGCAUCCAGACGGGAUCCAGUGCAUCCUCUUUUAGAAGAAAGGCCUGUCUCCAGAUCCCCGAGUCCCUCUAGCAUCUCCCAGAAGGUGUCAGACGCAGCAGUGUCCAGGGAGCGGCAGCAGAUUGAGGAAGAGUCUGGUGACACACCAGAAAAGGACAGGAUCAAGAGACUCUGACCCAUGGAUCCCCUGGGCCCGGCCAAGCCACAGUGGUCGUGGCGCUGCUGUCUGACCACGCUGCUGUUUCAGCUGCUGAUGGCUGUGUGUUUCUUCUCCUAUCUGCGUGUGUCUCAAGACGAUCCCACUGUGUACCCUAAUGGGUCCCGCUUCCCAGACAGCACAGGGACCCCCGCCCACUCCAUCCCCCUGAUCCUGCUGUGGACGUGGCCUUUUAACAAACCCAUAGCUCUGCCCCGCUGCUCAGAGAUGGUGCCUGGCACGGCUGACUGCAACAUCACUGCCGACCGCAAGGUGUAUCCACAGGCAGACGCGGUCAUCGUGCACCACCGAGAGGUCAUGUACAACCCCAGUGCCCAGCUCCCACGCUCCCCGAGGCGGCAGGGGCAGCGAUGGAUCUGGUUCAGCAUGGAGUCCCCAAGCCACUGCUGGCAGCUGAAAGCCAUGGACGGAUACUUCAAUCUCACCAUGUCCUACCGCAGCGACUCCGACAUCUUCACGCCCUACGGCUGGCUGGAGCCGUGGUCCGGCCAGCCUGCCCACCCACCGCUCAACCUCUCGGCCAAGACCGAGCUGGUGGCCUGGGCAGUGUCCAACUGGGGGCCAAACUCCGCCAGGGUGCGCUACUACCAGAGCCUGCAGGCCCAUCUCAAGGUGGACGUGUACGGACGCUCCCACAAGCCCCUGCCCCAGGGAACCAUGAUGGAGACGCUGUCCCGGUACAAGUUCUAUCUGGCCUUCGAGAACUCCUUGCACCCCGACUACAUCACCGAGAAGCUGUGGAGGAACGCCCUGGAGGCCUGGGCCGUGCCCGUGGUGCUGGGCCCCAGCAGAAGCAACUACGAGAGGUUCCUGCCACCCGACGCCUUCAUCCACGUGGACGACUUCCAGAGCCCCAAGGACCUGGCCCGGUACCUGCAGGAGCUGGACAAGGACCACGCCCGCUACCUGAGCUACUUUCGCUGGCGGGAGACGCUGCGGCCUCGCUCCUUCAGCUGGGCACUCGCUUUCUGCAAGGCCUGCUGGAAACUGCAGGAGGAAUCCAGGUACCAGACACGCGGCAUAGCGGCUUGGUUCACCUGAGAGGCUGGUGUGGGGCCUGGGCUGCCAGGAACCUCAUUUUCCUGGGGCCUCACCUGAGUGGGGGCCUCAUCUACCUAAGGACUCGUUUGCCUGAAGCUUCACCUGCCUGAGGACUCACCUGCCUGGGACGGUCACCUGUUGCAGCUUCACCUGCCUGGGGAUUCACCUACCUGGGUCCUCACUUUCCUGGGGCCUCACCUGCUGGAGUCUUCGGUGGCCAGGUAUGUCCCUUACCUGGGAUUUCACAUGCUGGCUUCCAGGAGCGUCCCCUGCGGAAGCCUGGCCUGCUGGGGAUGUCUCCUGGGGACUUUGCCUACUGGGGACCUCGGCUGUUGGGGACUUUACCUGCUGGGACCUGCUCCCAGAGACCUUCCACACUGAAUCUCACCUGCUAGGAGCCUCACCUGCUGGGGACCUCACCCUGGAGGGCACUGGGCCCUGGGAACUGGCACCCAUGGGGCCCCACCCAUGAGUGAUGGUUCUGGCUGAUUUGUUUGUGAUGUUGUUAGCCGCCUGUGAGGGGUGCAGAGAGAUAAUCACCGCACCGUUUCCAGAUGUAAUACUGCAAAGAAAACCAAUGAUGAGGCCGGGUGCGGUGGCUCACACCUGUAAUCCCAGCACUUUGGGAGGCCGAGGCAGGCGGAUCACAAGGUCAGGAGAUCGAGACCAUCCUGGCCAAUAUGGUGAAACCCGUCUCUAUUAAAAAUACAAAAAUUUGCUGGGCGUGGUGGUGCAUGCCUGUAAUCCCAGCUACUUGGGAAGCUGAGGCAGGAGAAUCGCUUGAACCAGAGAGUCGGAGGUUGCAGUAAGCCGAGAUCGCGCCACUGCACUCCAGCCUGGCGACAGAGCGAGACUCUGUCUCAAAAAAAAAAAAAAAAAAAAAAAAAAAAUUAGCUGGGUGCGGUGGCCGGUGCCUGUAAUCCCAGCUACCCAGGUGGCUGAGACACAAGAAUCGCUUGAACCCAGGAGGCAGAUGUUGUAGGGAGCCAUGAUCGCACCACUGCACUCCAACCUGGGCGACACAGUGAGACUGUCUCAAGAAAAAAAAAAAAAAGGGGGAGUGUCCCUUUCUGAGUGUGCAA